GAGCCCCUGUCUGGAUGACUUCUUGCGGCUGUUCUACCCCUCCCCCUCCCCGCGGUACCUUGCACUUUUCUCCCUCCCUGCCCCCUCUCGAGUCCACCCUCCGGGCCUUCUGCCCCUGAUCGCUUGGUUUUCCUUGCAGUCGCCUGCUGCUGUCGUCGGGAGGUGGGUGAGGUGACGCAAACAGCCCCGUUGUUGCCCUCCGCGUAUCCCCUCACCACCUUUGCGGCCAUCCACGACUUUCGCACCUUCCGCCAUUUUCCUGCCUGUGAGGGUGGACAGAUCGCGCUCGGGUCUCGGCCUCCUGAGUGCCGGUGACUGCGGGAGGCGACGGAGUGCUUCUGGGGGUGUGAGCUGGGGAAGUUCGUGGUCACGGAUGCGUGUGGGGUUGCUGCUCAGUCUGUAACGGCAGGUGGGAGACGGACACUGGGUGGAGGAUGGAGUGCGGAAAGAUGAAUGGGAGGGCUGAUUUUCGAGAGCCGAAUGCAGAGGUUCCAAGACCAAUUCCCCACAUAGGGCCUGAUUACAUUCCAACAGAGGAAGAAAGGAGAGUCUUCGCAGAAUGCAAUGAUGAAAGCUUCUGGUUCAGAUCUGUGCCUUUGGCUGCAACAAGUAUGUUGAUUACUCAAGGAUUAAUUAGUAAAGGAAUACUUUCAAGUCAUCCCAAAUAUGGUUCCAUCCCUAAACUUAUACUUGCUUGUAUCAUGGGAUACUUUGCUGGAAAACUUUCUUAUGUGAAAACUUGCCAAGAGAAAUUCAAGAAACUUGAAAAUUCCCCCCUUGGAGAAGCUUUACGAUCAGGACAAGCACGACGAUCUUCACCACCUGGGCACUAUUAUCAAAAGUCAAAAUAUGACUCAAGUGUGAGUGGUCAAUCAUCUUUUGUGACAUCCCCAGCAGCAGACAACAUAGAAAUGCUUCCUCAUUAUGAGCCAAUUCCAUUCAGUUCUUCUAUGAAUGAAUCUGCUCCCACUGGUAUUACUGAUCAUAUUGUCCAAGGACCUGAUCCCAACCUUGAAGAAAGUCCUAAAAGAAAAAAUAUUACAUAUGAGGAAUUAAGGAAUAAGAACAGAGAGUCAUAUGAAGUAUCUUUAACACAAAAGACUGACCCCUCAGUCAGGCCUAUGCAUGAAAGAGUGCCAAAAAAAGAAGUCAAAGUAAACAAGUAUGGAGAUACUUGGGAUGAGUGAAAAAUUACAUCAUUGGACAUGAAGGAGUUUCAACAUCCAGCUUCAUCUAGGUGGUCAUGAUUACCUGCAUGCUUUGAGCUCAGCAGCAGUCUUCAUAAACACAUUUAAAACAAGAUCCUGGGUUUUUGUGGUUUGACUUCUAUGGUGUUUUAAAAAAACACAGAUUUUUAGUGUUAAUAUUGUGUAAAUGUACUCACCUUAGGGAUUCAUUUGAAUGAUGGUAUUAUACCAUGAUUGUAUACAGUUUGUGAAAUUGUUGCAAGGGCAAAGAUAACUCUUAAAAAACCGUCGAGAUUACAAUGCUCUAGAAUCAGCAUAUAAGAAAAUAAAUGAUAUCUGCAUGUUGAAUUGGGGUGGAUGGGGGGAGCAAGCAUAAUUUUUAAGUGUGAAGCUUUGCAUCAAGAAAUUAUUAAAAAGCUUUUUUUCUCCAGUAUUUUCUGUAUUAUCUUAAUGUUUAUGGCAAAUAAAAUGUAAAGGAACAUGCAACAGCCCUCAUCUUCCUUGAUUUUAUGGUUUUAUUGUUUGUAAUUUAUUGAUUUAUUUUUAAGCUAGUUAUAAUCAUGUAGGUAUAGGAAAUAAAGUCAUCUAUAAUAUUUCUAUAAUAUGGCUAUAAUAUGGCUAUAAAUCUAUAAUAUGGCUGGAGGCAGUGGGCAGUGGUUCAUGCCUGUAAUCCCAGCACUUUGGGAGGCCGAAGUGGGAGGAUUGCAUGAGUCCAGGAGUUUGAGACCAGCCUGGGCAACAAAGCGAGACCCUGUCUUUACAAAAAAAUAAAAAUUAGCUGGCGAUGGUGUCGUGUGCCUGUAGUCCUAGUUACUUAAGAGGCUGAGUUGGGAGGAUCAGUUGAACCCAGUGGUUCUGGGUUGCAGUGAGCUGUGGUCACACCACUGAACUCCAGCCUGUGCGACUGAGUGAGACCCUGUGUCUAAAAAAAUAAAAAUAUAAUGAAUGUGAUUUAUGUAGAUAAAUUGAUAAUAUAGUAAAUAGGUAAAUGCCUUAAAAAGCAUUUUUAAAGAAUUUGUAAAUUCUAAAACAAUAAAAAUUUGGUAUACAUCA